GUAUCUCCCGAGCCGUUGCCACUGACAGCCGCGGGCGCUCCCAUCUGAGUAAGAGCCAGCCCGUCCGCGGCCUCUCCAGCCCCGGGUUCGCGCUCUCGACUCUCCUGCCUGCCCAGCUGCGCGGCGGAGCGGAGCGAGGCGCGGCCUGCGAGUCCCCGGCAGCCCCCGACCCCUCCCUCGGCGCUGCGUGUAGGCCGCGCCCUCAGGCCCAGUCCGCGGUGCCCCGGCGGGUGAUGCCAAAUACAGCCAUGAAGAAAAAGGUGCUGCUGAUGGGGAAGAGCGGGUCGGGGAAGACCAGCAUGAGGUCGAUAAUCUUCGCCAAUUACAUUGCUCGCGACACCCGGCGCCUGGGGGCCACCAUUGACGUGGAACACUCCCACGUCCGAUUCCUAGGGAACCUGGUGCUGAACCUGUGGGACUGUGGCGGUCAGGACACCUUCAUGGAAAAUUACUUCACCAGCCAGCGAGACAAUAUCUUCCGUAACGUGGAAGUUUUGAUUUACGUGUUUGACGUGGAGAGCCGCGAACUGGAAAAGGACAUGCAUUAUUACCAGUCGUGUCUGGAGGCCAUCCUCCAGAACUCUCCUGACGCCAAAAUCUUCUGCCUGGUGCACAAAAUGGAUCUGGUUCAGGAGGAUCAGCGUGACCUGAUUUUUAAAGAGCGAGAGGAAGACCUGAGGCGUCUGUCUCGCCCGCUGGAGUGUGCUUGUUUUCGAACGUCCAUCUGGGAUGAGACGCUCUACAAAGCCUGGUCCAGCAUCGUCUACCAGCUGAUUCCCAACGUUCAGCAGCUGGAGAUGAACCUCAGGAAUUUUGCCCAAAUCAUUGAGGCCGAUGAAGUUCUGCUGUUCGAAAGAGCUACAUUCUUGGUUAUUUCCCACUACCAGUGCAAAGAGCAGCGCGACGUCCACCGGUUUGAGAAGAUCAGCAACAUCAUCAAACAGUUCAAGCUGAGCUGCAGUAAAUUGGCCGCUUCCUUCCAGAGCAUGGAAGUUAGGAAUUCCAACUUCGCUGCUUUCAUCGACAUCUUCACCUCAAAUACGUACGUGAUGGUGGUCAUGUCAGAUCCGUCGAUCCCUUCUGCGGCCACUCUGAUCAACAUUCGCAAUGCCCGGAAACACUUUGAGAAGCUGGAGAGAGUGGAUGGCCCCAAGCACAGUCUCCUUAUGCGUUGAAUAUUGCCAAAUGCUCUUUCUGAAAAUGCUGAAUUGCCUUUUUUGUUUGCAUCCUUUAUUUUUAAUAUUCAUAAUGUCGUGUGCUUAAAAGUGGGCUUUGAAGUGUGUGCUGCUUACUCCUUUCAUCUUUCUCCCCGCUUCCCCAGUCUUUAAACAUUGGACGCUAUUUACUCAGCUACCCAGUAGAGCUUGAAGCUGACCUUUCUGAGAAGUUGGUAUGGUGUAACACUAAAGUAGGUGGUUCGUGUGUGUUCUCAUUACCUGGUUAUGAUAGAUAUGCACAUCAAAGCCUUUACCAGUAUCUUCCUGUAUUCCGUAUCAGAUUGCAAAGACGGAAUGUUACUAUUUUAUCAGCAAGGUAUUAAAAUGCAUUUAUAAAUUCUUCUUGGCUUCAUUCAUGAAUAAACGUGUUAGCAAUUUAAAA